GCUCGUUCCACAGGGACACCACGACGGCUCGCGGCCCCCAGCCUCUACCCCGCUCCGGAUCCGGGAUCUGAGCGCCGGCCGCGGUGCCCAGGCACUCCCUUGGCGGGCCGGAUGGCGGACCCCGGCCCAGAUCCCGAAUCUGAGUCGGAAUCGGUGUUCCCGCGGGAGGUCGGGCUCUUUGCAGACUCUUACUCGGAGAAGAGCCAGUUCUGUUUCUGUGGGCAUGUGCUGACCAUCACGCAGAACUUUGGGUCCCGCCUCGGGGUGGCGGCGCGCGUGUGGGACGCGGCCCUGAGCCUGUGCAAUUAUUUCGAGAGUCAAAAUGUGGAUUUCCGAGGCAAGAAGGUGAUCGAACUGGGUGCGGGGACAGGCAUCGUGGGGAUCUUGGCAGCGCUGCAGGGAGCUUAUGGUCUAGUGAGGGAGACAGAGGACGAUGUCAUAGAACAAGAACUCUGGCGAGGUAUGCGUGGAGCCUGUGGACAUGCUCUAUCCAUGUCUACCAUGACUCCCUGGGAAUCCAUCAAGGGAAGCUCUGUCAGGGGGGGAUGUUACCAUCACUGACCUGCCCCUGGCCCUAGAACAGAUCCAGGGCAACGUCCAGGCCAAUGUGCCAGCUGGAGGCCAGGCCCAGGUGCGUGCCUUGUCCUGGGGGAUUGACCAUCAUGUCUUCCCUGCAAACUAUGACCUGGUGCUGGGGGCUGAUAUCGUGUACCUGGAACCCACCUUCCCUCUGCUGCUGGGGACCCUCCAACACCUGUGCAGGCCCCAUGGCACCAUCUAUCUGGCCUCCAAGAUGAGAAAGGAGCAUGGGACAGAGAGCUUCUUUCAGCACCUCCUGCCCCAGCAUUUCCAACUGGAGCUGGCUCAGCGGGAUGAGGAUGAAAAUGUCAACAUCUAUAGGGCCAGGCACAGGGAACCAAGACCUGCUUGACAUCACCCUUGCUGUUCUUCUCAAUCUCUUGCUCUAAUGAAGGAACUGUGUAUCUCAAAAACCAUAUUUCCAGAGCCACAAACAUGAGGACCAAAAAGGAUGGAUUUCCCUGGCCUCUCUCACUUUCCUCCUUCCCUCUUUGUUACCCCAGAUACUCUUGGGCAGGUGCAGUGAGGUGCCUGCUUACAAGGAAUCCCAGAGUUCUGGCAGCACUAGUGUUAGAACACCAAGGAGGUUCCUGGCUCCUGUUCUCAGAGAAGGAGGAUGGUAAGGUAUCCAGGAUUUUUAGGGGGUAAGGGAGAUAUAUGGGAUGUGAGAGCAGUGAUUGUAGACAGACUGUCACUGAUCACUUCCAUUCCUGUUGCUGUUUACACAGAAUGGACUUUAAAAAAAUUCUGUGGGAUUUUUUUUUCUUUUUUUCUUUUUUUUUGAGACAGGGUCUCACUCUGUCAUCCAGGCUGGAGUGCAGUGGUGUGAUCACAGCUCACUGCAGCCUCAACCUCUGAAGGCCCAGAUGAUCUUCCUGCCUCAGCUCCCCAAGUAGCUGGGACUAGAGGCAUGCGCCACCACACCCGGCUAAUUUUUGUAUUUUCAGUAGAGACAGGGUUUCGCCAUGUUGCCCAGGGUGGUCUCAAACUCCUGGGCUCAAGUGAUCCACCCGCCUUGCCUCCCAAAGUGCUGGGAUUGCAGGCAUGGCCCACUGUGCUAGCCUAGGAUUUUUUUUUUUUUUUAAGAAAGAAUUAAGCCUUAAAAAUCUAUUGUGCAAGAACCCAACUUUUACUCAGGAGCUGAGAAGGAAGAAGCCUCAAACCACCCAUUUCCUGCUUUUUAGAGAUAGAGUCUAGUGGAACCAUGGCUCUAACUGGGUCAAGUCCUCCUAGCUCUGAAGCUAAGGCUGCAGAGCUGUCCUUUGGACUGUAUUUCUUCAUGCUUUCCAGAGUUAGAGCCUUGAUCACGGAACAUCAUUGUGUGCAGAAGAAUACUGUACCUAGUACUAAGUUCUUUUCAUCUUUGAUUUUUCUUUAGCUUCAUCAGUCCUUCCUUCCUAAUCUCUAAUCCCCUGAAGCCUAACACAGUUCCUAAUGUGUUUUGCCUUAACCUCUUUUCUCUUCCCACAUUGGUACUUCUGGUUGGGGCUCUCUUUACUUACUGCUUAGGCACAUAGUCACCUUCUCUGGACUCCCUGCUUCCAUGCUUUCUCCUUCAGUCCAUUCCGCAAACUCUUGUGAUCUUCCAAAAUUAGCUCUGAUUAGCUUUCACUUCCUGUAGAAGCAAGAACAAGCUCCUCUGCUUGGUACUUAGUCUGUGUCCAUGUGAUCCAAAAUUACCUUCCUAUUGCAUUUCCUACUCCUUUGCUACGUGUAUUGGACCUCUGGCCAAAUUACAAAAGAUGUACUCUUUGUUCUCUAAAACCACACUAAAGUUUUCUGACUUCUUUCACACUCUUUAUGAUAAUCCUCUGCCUGAAAGGCUAUUGCCACCUGUCAAAAUCUUCAUUAUUCUUUGCCUCUUUCCUGAGCCUCUUGCUUGAAUGUGAUUUCUUUCUCCCUGAGACCCAUAAGGUUCAUCUUAUGGGACCUUAAUUUGUCUUGCAUGGACAUUUGUGAUUCUCAUUUUCUCACCAUUAAAUUACCUUGGAGGGUAGGGCUGUGGUUUACUCCUGUCUAAACCCCUGAAGCCUAACACAGUUCCUGGCACACAACAGGUGUUCAACAGAUAUUGUGCUCAUUCAAUAAAUAUUUACUCGCUUUGUUUAAUGGAUUCCACCCCUGCCUUCCUAGGUGACCUUGGACAAAUUCUCGAACCCAUUCACCAACCACACAAGUUUGUUGUGAGUCAUAAAUGGAUAAUGAAUAUAAAUGCGCAUUGAAAAUAAACAUAAAAUGUUACCCACA